UGUAAUCCUAGCUCCUCGGGAGGCUAAGGUAGGAGAAUUGCUUGAACCUGGGAGGCAGAGAGGUUGGAGUGAGCCGAGAUUGCGCCAUUGCGCUCCAGCCUGAGCGGCAGAGCGAGACUCUGUCUCAAAAAAAUAAAUGUAAAUCGGACUCCCCUUCUUAAAGCCCUCAGUGGGGUCCCAUUGAUCAUUGCAUAAAAUCCAAUUUCUUUAACAAGUCUUCUCCCCUCACCCGCUUCGGACCACUGCCUGCCUUGCCUAAGUCCUUUCUUAUGACCUCUUUCCCACCUCUGCCGGCUGGGUUCCCUCUACUUGGGAAUGCUCUUCACCCCAUCAUUUAGACAGCAGGUUCCUUUUGGCCCUCUGGGUCUCAUUUAUAUGUUACUUUUUAAGUAUAUUCCAAAGGUCACCCCUAUUUUUCUGUCUCAUACUUAUAAAAUGUAAUGAAUGUCUAACUCAUCUUGGCUAUUAAAAUUUUUAUGUGUGGGUCUGUCUCUUCUGCCCUGAAAUUAGCUCUGCUAGGGUAGAAACUAUAUUGUUAACGCCUCAUUCCCAGUUUUUGGUACAUAAUAGCUGCCCAGUAAGUUAUUGAAUGAAUGAACUCCAGGGGGUAAGCAUGAUAUCCAUUUCACAGACUAAAAAACUGAGGCUCAGCAGUUAACUAACCUGCCCAAGUGCACAUUUACUCCCUAGUCAUGGCCGGGUUUGAGACAAGGGACCAUGUUUGCCUAUUACUGGCCACACAGGAACUCAAUUGAGGAGCAUGGCCUCCAGGCCCAGCUGAUGGUCUUUAAGCUCAAUGAGAAGGAGCAGCUGGAGGUGAAAGAGAAAUGCCCCAGCUGGGUCUCAUAUAGUGGGGAGUGAGGAAACACUAGUAGCUCUAAAUGGAGUACCCUUUUAUAUCCACAACAUGUUUUAAAGUCCUUAAUAAAAGUGCUAACAGUGUCCUGAGCUAGCAUUUGGUGGGAAGAUUUCUUAGAUUUUUCAUGUUAGUGCAGUGUUUGCCAAAUUUCACUCACACUCACCUGCCUUCUCCCCAGUUUGCUUUAUUCUCUUAACACAUGACACAGGAUUUAUUUCAGGGCCGCUUUGCCAGCUGGAGACCUCCAGCCCUGGGCUGGCUGCAGGAGGUGCCCUGCCCACUCAGCCUGGCAGAAUGCAUUUGUCUUUCAUCCCCGCCCAGAUCCCGUGGCCACUAUGACUGCAUGCUCAGCCCGCGAGGAGUCGGUUUGUGAGUGAGUGAGCAAGCCUGGAGGCCCGGCUGGCUGUUCCAAGUGCUGGCCCAGUCACAGGCUCCAUGUAGGGCUUGUGGAUGGCCUGGGUGUAUGGCAAGUGACUCUGGUAGCAGAUUCUGGUGUCCAGACGAGGGGGAUGCAGUAGUGCCCAAACACUUGGAGACACCAGGCAAAUAGAGAUGUAUUAACAGCUCUUUUAGUCCCACCAUCUGCAGCCCAAUGAAUGGGGGUGUGUGGCAGCCAGCAGCUCCCUCUCCCAUUGCUUCACUAGCGGAACGGAGUGCUACAGGGUUAUAGCUCUAUUUGCACUCGCUGUUUAGCUGGUCCGAAUUUCUUGUCCUGCGUCCAAGAAUAAUGAGGUUAGGCUGACAACCGAAGGGGAAAAGGGCGGAGGAGUAUAAUGUCUCAGGAAGGCGAUUAUGGGAGGUGGACCAUAUCUAGUAGUGAUGAAAGUGAGGAAGAAAAGCCAAAACCAGACAAGCCAUCUACCUCUUCUCUUCUCUGUGCCAGGCAAGGAGCAGCAAAUGAGCCCAGGUACACCUGUUCCGAGGCCCAGAAAGCUGCACACAAGAGGAAAAUAUCACCUGUGAAAUUCAGCAAUACAGAUUCAGUUUUACCUCCCAAAAGGCAGAAAAGCGGUUCCCAGGAGGACCUCGGCUGGUGUCUGUCCAGCAGUGAUGAUGAGCUGCAACCAGAAAUGCCGCAGAAGCAGGCUGAGAAAGUGGUGAUCAAAAAGGAGAAAGACAUCUCUGCUCCCAAUGACGGCACUGCCCAAAGAACUGAAAAUCAUGGCGCUCCCGCCUGCCACAGGCUCAAAGAGGAGGAAGACGAGUAUGAGACAUCAGGGGAGGGCCAGGACAUUUGGGACAUGCUGGAUAAAGGGAACCCCUUCCAGUUUUACCUCACUAGAGUCUCUGGAGUUAAGCCAAAGUAUAACUCUGGAGCCCUCCACAUCAAGGAUAUUUUAUCUCCUUUAUUUGGGACGCUUGUUUCUUCAGCUCAGUUUAACUACUGCUUUGACGUGGACUGGCUCGUAAAACAGUAUCCACCAGAGUUCAGGAAGAAGCCAAUCCUGCUUGUGCAUGGUGAUAAGCGAGAGGCUAAGGCUCACCUCCAUGCCCAGGCCAAGCCUUACGAGAACAUCUCUCUCUGCCAGGCAAAGUUGGAUAUUGCGUUUGGAACACACCACACGAAAAUGAUGCUGCUGCUCUAUGAAGAAGGCCUCCGGGUUGUCAUACACACCUCCAACCUCAUCCAUGCUGACUGGCACCAGAAAACUCAAGGAAUAUGGUUGAGCCCCUUAUACCCACGAAUUGCUGAUGGAACCCACAAAUCUGGAGAGUCGCCAACACAUUUUAAAGCUGAUCUCAUCAGUUACUUGAUGGCUUAUAAUGCCCCUUCUCUCAAGGAGUGGAUAGAUGUCAUUCACAAGCACGAUCUCUCUGAAACAAAUGUUUAUCUUAUUGGUUCAACCCCAGGACGCUUUCAAGGAAGUCAAAAAGAUAAUUGGGGACAUUUUAGACUUAAGAAGCUUCUGAAAGACCAUGCCUCAUCCAUGCCUAACGCAGAGUCCUGGCCUGUCGUAGGUCAGUUUUCAAGCGUUGGCUCCUUGGGAGCCGAUGAAUCAAAGUGGUUAUGUUCUGAGUUUAAAGAGAGCAUGCUGACACUGGGGAAGGAAAGCAAGACUCCAGGAAAAAGCUCUGUUCCUCUUUACUUGAUCUAUCCUUCUGUGGAAAAUGUGCGGACCAGUUUAGAAGGAUAUCCUGCUGGGGGCUCUCUUCCCUAUAGCAUCCAGACAGCUGAAAAACAGAAUUGGCUGCAUUCCUAUUUUCACAAAUGGUCAGCUGAGACUUCUGGCCGCAGCAAUGCCAUGCCACAUAUUAAGACAUAUAUGAGGCCUUCUCCAGACUUCAGUAAAAUUGCUUGGUUCCUUGUCACAAGCGCAAAUCUGUCCAAGGCUGCCUGGGGAGCAUUGGAGAAGAAUGGCACCCAGCUGAUGAUCCGCUCCUACGAGCUCGGGGUCCUUUUCCUCCCUUCAGCAUUUGGUCUAGACAGUUUCAAAGUGAAACAGAAGUUCUUCGCUGGCAGCCAGGAGCCAAUGGCCACCUUUCCUGUGCCAUAUGAUUUGCCUCCAGAACUGUAUGGAAGUAAAGAUCGGCCAUGGAUAUGGAACAUUCCUUAUGUCAAAGCACCGGAUACGCAUGGGAACAUGUGGGUGCCCUCCUGAGAAUCUUGAGGCACUGUGAAAUUUAAGUGUAAGACAUUGAGCCACAAACAUGGAAUCUCUUCUUUGUACUGGAUGUCCACUUCCCUUAAAGUCUUAUUUGCACCCUUACAAAAUCUUUCCAAAGGUCACUCUUAUGAAUGGAUGUUGGUUAUACUUUUAAUGGACAUUAACAUUCCUAAUAAAGUAUUAGUUUCUUAAUUCACUUUUAUAUGUUUUGGAAAGAAAAUUAGUGAACUUCUCUAUGUUAAAAAUACGUACUGCUUGAGUAUCCCCUGUCUGAAAUGCUUGGGACCAGAAGUGUUUCAGCUUUUGGAUUUUUUUGAAUUUUGGAAUAUUUGCAUAGCAUAAUGAGAUAUCUUGGGAAUGGGACCCAAAUCUAAACACAAAAUUCAUUUAUGUUUCAUAUACACCUUAUAUACAAUAACCUAAAGGUGAUUUUAUAUGAUAUUUUGAGUAAUUUUAUGCAUGAAACAAAGUUUUGACAGGCUUUUGACCGUGAUUCAUCACAUGAGUUCAGGCAUGGAAAUUUUCAUUUGGAGCAUCAUGUCAGCACUCAAAAAGUUCUGGAUCUUGGAGCAGUUCAGAUUUUCAGAUUAGGGAUGCUCAAAUCUAUAUAGAUAUAAAAUUAUCCUCACAGUAACAUAGAAUCUCUUGGUGCUGUCAGCUGUUGGGAAUUGAAGAUUGACUUUGUGCUUCCACCCUCCAUCCAGAAAGGCACCCUUCAUUCCACCAGAACUUUACCCAGGAAGAACACGAUCAUUUCCUUUUUCACCGAUGCCCUCUCUCAGCUUUCUGAGUACGUCUCUUGGGGUCGCUGGAGGUGAUCCUAGGAUCUGUCUCUGAGACCAAUGUGCUGUUUCAGCCCCCUGCAGCUAAGAAUUGUAUUGACUGUCCUCACAGCGGCUUUUCAUAGCUUUCAGCUUCAGCUUUACGAGGCUUCUCCUCUCUCCCUGGCACCCUGCUGGCUGCCUCACUGCUUACAGACAGGUCCCACCAAACCCAAACACCUGCCUAGGGUAAAUGGGUCUCUCUUCUAUCCCCAGAAACUUUCAGAGGAAGCAGCUCAUAGAAACAUACAAAAGCACACAAGUAUUUUGGGAAAAAAUCCUAAAAGGUGACUUAAUUUGAUGCCUUAAAUUCACAAGUGAGGAAGCUAAGGCCUAGAAGGUUAAGGAUGUCCCCAGGGUCACACAGUGAGCGGGGCUCAGAGCUUGAGUGUCUUUGUGCUUUGUGUACAUUGUGUUCUCCCUAGGGUGCUUUAGACCCUGUUUGUUUUCUUCUGCAUGAGGCUGAUUUCCAGUUUGUCAUCAACCUCUUUAUCUUAUAAUUUAGGAUAGAGUUGAACGUUAGUCUUGAAAGAUUUUCUAAAGUAGUCUUUCAAACUGUUCCUCAGAGGCCUAGGAUUUUCCAAAAGUACCUUAGGAACCUUGUAGGCUGCAGUGGGGGUGUGGCGAUAGAGCAGGAGGCAGGGAGACAGGGCUGCAGGGCCUCCCACCUUCCAACAGACAGGCUCUGCUGUAUCUGUUGUACAUACUGGGAUUCUGUAAAGGACAUUAUCUGGGGUGUUGUAUGUAUUUUUGUGUGUUCUGCUUUUUUUAAAUAAACUUGAAAAGCUACUGAA